AAGACAGGCAUCUCAAAUCGGCUGAUUCUGCAUCUGGAAACUGCCUUCAUCUUGAAAGAAAAGCUCCAGGUCCCUUCUCCAGCCACCCAGCCCCAAGAUGGUGAUGCUGCUGCUGCUGCUUUCCGCACUGGCUGGCCUCUUCGGUGCGGCAGAGGGACAAGCAUUUCAUCUUGGGAAGUGCCCCAAUCCUCCGGUGCAGGAGAAUUUUGACGUGAAUAAGUAUCUCGGAAGAUGGUACGAAAUUGAGAAGAUCCCAACAACCUUUGAGAAUGGACGCUGCAUCCAGGCCAACUACUCACUAAUGGAAAACGGAAAGAUCAAAGUGUUAAACCAGGAGUUGAGAGCUGAUGGAACUGUGAAUCAAAUCGAAGGUGAAGCCACCCCAGUUAACCUCACAGAGCCUGCCAAGCUGGAAGUUAAGUUUUCCUGGUUUAUGCCAUCGGCACCGUACUGGAUCCUGGCCACCGACUAUGAGAACUAUGCCCUCGUGUAUUCCUGUACCUGCAUCAUCCAACUUUUUCACGUGGAUUUUGCUUGGAUCUUGGCAAGAAACCCUAAUCUCCCUCCAGAAACAGUGGACUCUCUAAAAAAUAUCCUGACUUCUAAUAACAUUGAUGUCAAGAAAAUGACGGUCACAGACCAGGUGAACUGCCCCAAGCUCUCGUAACCAGGUUCUACAGGGAGGCUGCACCCACUCCAUGUUACUUCUGCUUCGCUUUCCCCUACCCCCCCCCCAUAAAGACAAACCAAUCAACCACGACAAAGGAAGUUGACCUGAACAUGUAACCAUGCCCUACCCUGUUACCUUGCUAGCUGCAAAAUAAACUUGUUGCUGACCUGCUGUGCUCGCAGUAGAUUCCAA